GCGGGCCGUAGUCGAGCCUGGUGGGCGGCUGGCUGGCAGGGGACGUGGUCGGCGGCAGCGGGGCCCAGGGGCGGCGGGGCUGCAGCAGCGGCGGCCCCAGCUUCGCCGAGCAGCGAUCGGCUGGUGGGCUUCUCGUUGGCGGGCUCCGCGUUGGCGGGCUGCUCCCCAGGCACCAGCGCAGCGCGCGCUCGCCCGGCUUCGUCACUCGCCUCCAGCUACAUCCGCCGGCCGAGGCUGCGCGAGCCUCCGGGCUUGCGGUCCCCGCCCCGCGGUCCUUCCUCCACCCUCAGCCAGGGCAGCUGCAGCCCGAGCGAACAGCCACGGAGCAUCCUCCGCCCGCCCGGGCCGCGCCACCGCCCAUGCUGCAGCCAGUCCCAGGCAGCGACCCCGCGGCCGCAGCCCGCCGCUCAGUGACCUCAGCCUGGCCCCUGCGCGCCGCCCGAGCCGGUCCCGCUGAGCCGCGGGCCCCGUGCCCUGCGAUGGCUCGGCUGGUGCAGCGCGGCGCCAGGUGCCAGCCGUCCUCCCGCUGAGACGCGCCCGAGUGGGGACCCGCUGGGCCUCGGGGCUCGCAGCCUUCGCCUCCCCGCCGCGCCCGCUCCCUUUCUGGGGACUCCGCCGCUGUUUCUGGGGACGAGGGGACAGGGGACCCAGACAAAGCCCACUUUGUGCAGGGAGUUGGCCGCAGGCGGGGAAUGUGCGCGUCGGCGCGCGCCCCCUCCCCGCUCCCGGCCAGCUGCGAGUCUUGGCUCCCGGACUUGUCUCGUCGCGUCGGAGAAAUCGCCCCCCAGCGCCGCUCUCCCGCCCGGGGGUCUUGGUUCCGAGCUCGCGCGGCCGGGAGUCGCCUCGGUCUUCCUUGGGGCGCGCGCAGAUGUGAGCGUGCGAGAGUUGUGUAGGGGAUUUUGUUCCCUCCGAAACUGAGACCCAGGGCGCCCAGUGGGCACCCGUGCCUUGACUCUGUCCUUUCUGCAGCCGCUGGUCCGAGCUGUCUGGCCUCAGUUUCCCUCCGACUUUUCUCCGCUCUGCCAGCCCUCACUGCUGCCCGUCAUUGUUCUCGCAGUUAGAUGGGGGUGCUUUGUGACGGCUGCCAAGUUGGGGUGUGUUCUCUUUAUUCCGUUUUUCAAACAGAACAAGGCCUCCAAGGCUGACCCCAGACAACCCACCCCCUCGGACCCUAAUUCACCUUAUUGCACUGAUUUUUUUUAUCAAGUCGUAUUUUAUUGUACAGGAGCCACGCCCUGAUUUCUUAAAGGCGCCUUGCACUCUGGCCAUGUGUUAUCUCUGCAGCCGGUGUGUGGGAGGCCUCUUGUGAGCCAGUUGUUUUCCCGCCUCCACCACCCCCCUCGAAGAUUUAGGGAUGCCAGGGGGGAAGAAGGUGGCUGGGGGUGGCAGCAGCGGUGCCACUCCAACGUCCGCUGCGGCCACCGCCCCCUCUGGGGUCAGGCGUUUGGAGACCAGCGAAGGAACCUCAGCCCAGAGAGAUGAGGAGCCAGAAGAGGAAGGGGAAGAGGACCUGCGAGACGGAGGCGUCCCCUUCUUUGUCAACCGGGGUGGGCUACCUGUGGAUGAGGCCACCUGGGAAAGGAUGUGGAAACACGUGGCCAAGAUCCACCCCGAUGGAGAGAAGGUGGCGCAACGGAUCCGUGGGGCCACAGACCUGCCCAAGCCUUGUGACGUAAGUACAGUUUGGAUUCCCAUUUUACAGAUGAGAAAGCUGAAAACUCAAGUAGGAACUCAAGAUCCCACAGCCAGUGUGGAGCUGGCAGGAAAGAGAAGACUUGGAGGAGGACCCGGCCCCUCUGUGCAUGCCCCAGCCACAGAGCUACAGCAAGACCUGUUCCAAAAUAUGUCCUUCUGGCCUGCUACCGCUGACUGACUCCUUGACAGUUCAAGUUGGUGCUCUGGAAGGCAUGGCGAAUAUGCCCAUGAUACUGGAUCCCCAUACCGAGUGUGCCUACGUUCCAGCCGUCUACACCUGUCCCUGAGCGCCUGGAAGCUGUGCAGCGCUACAUCAGAGAGCUGCAGUACAAUCACACAGGGACACAGUUCUUUGAAAUUAAGAAGAGCAGACCUCUGACAGGGCUGAUGGACCUGGCCAAGGAAAUGACCAAAGAGGCCCUGCCAAUCAAAUGCCUGGAAGCCGUGAUCCUGGGAAUUUACCUCACCAACAGCAUGCCCACCCUGGAGCGCUUCCCCAUCAGCUUCAAGACCUACUUCUCAGGGAACUACUUCCGCCACAUCGUGCUGGGGGUGAACUUCGCGGGCCGCUACGGUGCGCUGGGCAUGAGUCGGCGCGAGGACCUGAUGUACAAGCCGCCCGCCUUCCGCACGCUCAGCGAGCUCGUGCUGGACUUCGAGGCCGCCUACGGCCGCUGCUGGCACGUGCUCAAGAAGGUGAAGCUGGGCCAGAGCGUGUCACACGACCCGCACAGCGUGGAGCAGAUCGAGUGGAAGCACUCGGUGCUGGACGUGGAGCGCCUGGGCCGCGAUGACUUCCGCAAGGAGCUGGAGCGCCACGCCCGCGACAUGCGGCUCAAGAUUGGCAAAGGGACGGGCCCUCCCUCUCCCACCAAGGACCGGAAGAAGGAUGUUUCUUCCCCGCAGCGGGCCCAGUCCAGCCCCCACCGCAGGAACAGCCGCAGUGAAAGACGGCCCUCGGGUGACAAGAAGACUUCCGAGCCCAAAGCCAUGCCAGACCUUAACGGGUACCAGAUCCGGGUCUGAGGCGGAUGCCAGCACCCCAGGCCCCACCCACUCUUGGGGGCCAGGAUCCACCUGCUGGAACCAGCCUUAUGCAUGGGGAAGGCGGGGCUGGUGACAAGGCAGGGCAAGAGGCUGCAGGAAGAGUGUGUUCCAGCUCAGCCCCCCAAGCUGCUCUCGCUCCCACUGAGCCAAGCCCCCUAACUUUGGGCCUAGAGGCCGUUAGUAUUUUAUUUGGAGUUUUUAACUCUACAACUGAAGUUUAAGGUAUUUGGGGAAAACUUAGUCCAAAUGGAUCUGCUGAUGGUGGGAAGGCCAGUGCUUAACAAAUCCAUGUGUCAUGGGGCCAGGUGAGGGAAACUGCUGGUUCUGCUGGUGCCUCUGCCCCUGGCUUCUCUCUGGGAGUUGGGUGCAUCUUAUCAGUGGGAAAUCUCCCAGCCUUACCAGGCCUGUGAUGGGGGGUGGGGGUGGGGUGGAGAUGUUUCUCCAGUUCUGCCUGCCCUGGCAGAAUCUUGACCCAGGGAAAGGGAAGCAGGGUAGGAGUCCUUCUGAGAAAGGUCUGUGUAGCCCAUUAACCAGGAGCUUGGCACAGGCCACAUCUGCCCCAAGAGCAUGAGCUCGUGGCUCAGGAGAGCCUUCAGGCCCUUGAGGCCCCCAUGGGCAGUGCUGUGUGGGCAGAGGAGGGGUGAUAUGAGAGCGAGCCCAGGGAAGGACCUCUGGGCAAAAAGUUCCCAGGCCCUAACUGCGUCUACUUGCUCAGUCCCAGCUCUGCCUGUUGCUCUAGCCCACAGGCUCCCUGCGGAGGGUCUGGGCUUGGCGGAGGACCCAGAAUGGCACUGAGGCCAGCAUGGCUGUGGGAGUUGAGCAAACCCUGGGUGCCAGUCCAGGAGCUGUGGCUGGACAUGGGGUGAUGGGGCGGGAUGCUUGGGCCUGGGUCUCUCCGCCAGCAGUGCCAGGAGCCCUUGCUGGGGAAAUCAAGACCAGACUAGGAUGCUUCUGCCCCAGGCCUGCCUUCCAUUCUUUAACAGCCCAUCUUGGCUUGGGGUUGCAAUGAUGGCUGGGCCAGUCACUUGUGGCAGGGCAUCAGGGCCCUGGCAGGGAAGAACCUAGGCACCUGGGGUUGUCCCCAGCCUGCCCGUCAGCAUGAGAUACCCAGUGGGAAAGUGAGAGGAUGCGGAGAGGUUGGCAGAGCCAGGGGUAGGUUCUGGAGGCUCAAGCAACAAGGAGGUGCAGGUAAAGGGUGCAGUGCAGCCACUGAGGGACAGCUGGGAACUGGGGGAUGCAAGUGAGAAAGGGAUGUGGGGGAGAGUUCAGGAUCAGGCUGCUUGAGGAGUAAUGGGUUACCUACAGCAGAGACGAGAUGGCUGUUUGUCAGGAGGCGGUAGAAAGGUAGAAAGGAUUCAGAUUGUGGAAGGGUAAACGGAUGAGAUGACCAUUAAGGUUUUGUUUUACUGAGAGGCUGUAAGUCUGCCAGGGACAGCUGUCAGUAAGGCUGCAGAAGGGCUGGGGGGCUACACAAGGAAGAGCAGAACUAGGGUUGUAAGCUCAAAUGACGAGCAAACGGUGAGAAGGAGGCCUGAAGGGCUGUGUGGGGACUAUGGCUACCUGAAGAGGGCACACCCUGUUAAAGGGGCCACAGCUGCUCAGCUGUUCUUACAGUGCCGGCCCUGUGUUGCCAGAUUGUCUGCUUUGUCAGAGGCCAGAAUUCUGACUUUUUAUGUGAAAUAGGAUUUUUAAAUGCUGGUGAUCACUUAAAAAAAACUUAAAAACCCAAUACUGGCAAAAGAGGAUGCCAGUUUGCAAUCCCUGAAGUAGAGAGAGCUCGUGCUGGGGAGAAGUCCACCAAGAUGCUUUGAGGCGGGCUGUAGCAAAGUCCUGUUUCUCAGAGCUGGGCUGGGCUGGGGUAGGAUCCUUGCAGCUGAGGAGGAGGAAAAGCCACUGAGUCUCCUCCCAGAGCGGGACAAACCAGAGGCCCUUUGCAGUUGCUGGGUCACCAGCGGGGGUGGCGCAUGGAGUACAGACAGUGUAGCUCUUGGCCUGCCAGGGAGACGGAUGGUGCCUUUGAAGCAAAGAGGAAGGGAAGGCAGAACCAGGGAUGCCUUUGCUGAUGAGAGUGCCUGUCAGGGAAGGCGCCACAGGCUGGCAGCUCUUCAAACCAGCAGCGCUUGACCCAGAGCCAGAUCCAGCAUGGCCUGGCCAGAGGCACCCUGGGAGGCCAGCUGGUCAGUCCCUUGCCUCCCCAAGUUCCCCCUGGGGUCAAUGAGCCCUGGGAGGAUGCCUAACCUAACUCCAGCCAGACUAAUAGGGGCAUGGUGACCCUUGACUCACCAUCCCAUCCCAGCUUUCAGGGAGUGGGGGUAGUGUGGUCUCCAUGUUCCUACUAUGCCUAAGAAGAGAUGGCUCACCUUGGGAGGUGCCAGGCUGAAACUAGGUCCUUUCCGGGUCUGGAUGCUGCCGCUCAGGAGCAGGGGCGUGGCCUCAGCUGCCUCUGGGAGCUUCCCGGGAAUGACAGGGUUUGAGGGGAGUAGAUAUGAGAGGGAGCCGCUCCUGGUUCUGGAGUCUUAGGAGGUUCCAACUUGCAGGAUCCUUUCCCAGAGCCCUCCAUGGAGAAAACAGCAAAAUGAAGCCCUUACCUGCUUGCUGUCUGCAAGGGAGGGAGCCGAGCCCCAGCUGAUAAUCCCCCAGCACUCACCCUUCCUGAGCUGAGACUUCGGGGCUGUGGAGACCAGCACAGGACAUAGUGGUGCUUUUUAAAUUUAUUUUUAACUGUUUCUCAUAUGUAGCAACCCCUCCUCCCCUCCUGGGCAUGUUUACACAGGCUCUGCUCUGGGGGCUGGCCUGGCUGUGAGGUUUCUGGGGAGGCAGAGAGGCAGGGACUUUGGGGCCUUAGUCACCAUCCAUGGUAUCACCUCAUCUCACUUCCUGUGAGGGACAGGGCCUGGCUGAUGUGAUCCCAGCUCCCCCCAGUUCAGGACUGUCUUUCAGCUCCUUUGCCCCUGGAGGUGGGGGCUGCUGGCUGAGGAGGGGUCAAGGUGAGUUCAAGAAAGCUACCUGUGGAAAAUGGACCAGGUUGGGGGGGUGAUUGCAAAGUCUCCCCAAAGCCUGGCUCCUCAUGCUCAGUGCCAGGGGCAGAACACUGGGGAGCCAGGUAUAGAGAGCCUUCCUGUCAUAACUGCCAGUCCUCUUCCUCCAAGGCCUCUGCAUAUUCUCAUGUUCCCCUCACCCAUCAUGCCAGCCACCCCUAUCCCUCUUCUAGCAGGGCCAAGAUGGGGACAGCAGCAGCCCUCUGGCCUUGGGAUGUGAUGAUAAAGCAAGCCUAGGGCCAGGGUUUGGGGAGCAGAGAGAGCCAAGAAGUUGACCACGUGUGAUUUCCAGCCCUUCCCACUGGGACUUGACUUCCCAGGUCAAGGAGUCCGUCUCAUUCUGGCUGGUCGAGUGACCAGAGGCCUGUGUGAAUGUGUGCACCUGCUUUUCCUGCCUGGAAUGUUUUCUGGCUCAGCUGCAGCAACAUCUGUGAGCCCAGUGUCUGCCCUGUGUCCCUGGGCUCGCUCCAAGUGCAGGAACAUACAUGCAGGGCCCAACAUGAUGAUGGUGUGAAGGGCAGGAAACAGUCCUCUGAAGGAGUGGGGAGGUGGGCAGUCUGCCCCCGCCAGGUACCAUCGCCUCCUGCCAGCUUCCUUAGACCAGGCAGGGCUGCCAUGGUGCUAGCUGCAAGUCCAUCAGUAUUGACCGUCUCGCUCCAUCUUGGUCCUCCGGAGUCCCAAGUUUCCUUUUCAUCAAAUCUGACAAGAGAGAAGAAACAUGGGUGUGCUUGGCCCACAGGGCCUGGUGGUGAUGGACCUCCCCGCUCCCUCAAGCUCUGGAUGGCUGCAGUGUUGUACUAGACUUUGUUCAGGCUGUUCUCAUCUCAGUAUUGCCCCUUCCUUUCACUUUCACACUUCAUCUCAUUCCUGUUGUCACUUUCCCCGAAACGAAUAAAGUCUCCCCAGCUCCUGCUGUGUAGGCUGGGCAGAAACCACAA